GCAGCUGCUCUUCCUUACCCAGACGGGACAGUCGUGGACCACCAGCUUGACAUUCCCAAACGCACUGGCCUGAUACUCGGUGAACACCGGACGCGCGACCGUGCUGGCCGCGUUCAGCAACAAGCUGCUCUCGUCCCCGGAGACCAGAGGGCUUCUCCCCAGGUAAGUGCGGAUAAGCCCCGACGGCCGGUUGUCCUGGUGGAAUGUGUCCCCCUCGUUCCCCAGCGCCACGAUGUGGAUGGACCUGCACGGACAGAGGGGGCGAGGGGAGAAGGGAAGCACGGUCAGCGCGCGGGUCUCUCCUCGGAACAGGAAGUGCGGGGGACAGCGCGCGGCGAGGAUGGGCACCAGCCCCUGUCCCUGGGGCGCACGGCACGCGCUGGAGAGAGACAAUGGCAGGACGGCGGCGCGUUCAGCCAUUUAGGAAAGAUUGGUGACCUAUCUGCAUGAUGGCAUUAACUACAAGGAUCAUCGAAGAGCCACAGUCACAAAGCCAGUCUCUGAAUAUGGUUCAAAGAAAUCUUAUAACUCUCUGAACAGAAGCAACCGAAUAUAUGGACCCCAUGACCCAGCUGUAUUAGUCUGUUCUCAUGCUGCUAAUAAAGACAUACCUGAGACUGCAUAAUUUAUAAAGGGAAGAGGUUUAAUGGACUCACAAUCAUGGCAGAAGGUGAAGGAGCAAAGGCAUGUCUUACAUGGUGGCAGGACGUGUAUUCGUCAACACUACUUGGAGGGCCGGUACUUCCAAGGAAGUCACCUUUGCAGUCGAUCUAUGUGCACUGUUCUCAGAGCCAGCUCGCACCCAUGAAGAACAACACAACUUACCGGUCAUAGGAGCAGAAAGUGUCAACCUUGCAGCAGGAUUUGGACACUCUGGGAGCCAAACUGGAUGUGGAAGCUCCAAAGAGGAUGCAGCAAUAAGGCACCAUCUUGGAAAAGGAGACUGAUCCUCAAAAAAUGUCAGUGCCUCAAUCUUGGACUUCCCAGCCUCUAAAACGGUUUACAAAGUCCUCUUGGAGAAGCAGAUUCCUGUGGGAACCUGGUUAAAUCUCCCAAGCUAGCAGUGUUUUUACUACAAUAAGACAGUGAUUAAUUGUGUCCCACUGGGCACUGUCCUGAUAAGUUUUGCUCCAGGCUUGGAAGUCUACAGUGGAAGAGUGAGGGAACUUUGGUCAGCUGCUUUUCCUCUCCUCAGCUCUCCUCCCUCAUCGGUUUCUGCUUUUGGCCUCUUCAAAGCUGCAAGAGGGAAGGAGAAAAGGAUUUCCCAAGCUUGGCCAACCUAUGAUUGAAAGUGGGAUCACAAGAAUAAUGAUAACCUGGAUUUCACUGGUUUUGCCCCAUCUGCAAAACUUCAAGUCUCUACAAAGGCCUGAAUCUGCUGUCUCCUAAGUAUUUUUGGGAAUUCCCAUGGGGUGUCUAAUUAUCAGGAACAAAUCUGUCGAGGGGAUCCAGAAAGCAAUCAUGGACCUUGUAGAUGAGUUUAAAGAUGAAUUUCCCACCAUCCUAAGAUUAUCACAGUCUAAUCAGAAAAGAGAACCUGCGCAGAAAACAUCCAAAAUCAGGAUGGCUAUUGCUUUAGCUAAGAUUAAUCGAGCAACAUUAAUUCGUGGAUUAAACAGCAUAUCCAGAUCCUCCAAAUCAGUGGCCAAACUUCUGCAUCCUCAGCUUGCAUGCAGACUUUUAGAGCUAAGGGACAUAUCUGGUCGUCUGCUGAGGGAAGUUAAUGCGCCGAGGCAACCCCUAUAUAACAUUCAGGUCAGAAAGGGUUCUUUGUUUGAAAUCAUCUCCUUUCCAGCAAAGACUGCUUUAACUAGCAUAAUAUAUGCUUCAUAUGCAGCACUAAUUUAUUUGGCAGUCUGUGUUAAUGCUGUGCUGAAGAAGGUAAAGAACAUCUUCCAGGAAGAAGAAUCCAUAAGGCAAAACAGAGAGGAGAGUGAAAAUUGUAGAAAAGCCUUUUCUGAGCCUGUGCUUUCGGAGCCUAUGUUUGCUGAAGGUGAAAUCAAAGCAAAACCUUAUAGGUCAUUGCCGGAGAAGCCAGACAUUUCAGAUUACCCCAAGCUUCUUGCUAAUAAGCAGAGUAAUAACAUCCAAGUUUUACAUUCUGUGUUUGACCAAUCAGCUGAAAUGAAUGAGCAAAUCUGAAUACAGGUAUCACUGAACAGAACUUAAGAGUUAUCUAUUUAAUGGCACAUUUCAUCUGACAAAACUCAGAGUCUAGUUUACAUAUUCUGAAUUGCUCUGCUUUCUUAAAAAAAAGAGAAGGGGGCUACUAUUAAAAUGUCAUUUUCUAGUAUUUACAUGAUAGAGUAAAUAAAAUGAAUAUUGAUGUGGAAUAUAUGUACUGACUACAUACUUUUAAUGAACAAGAAAAUCCAUCCUCUGGUAGGUUAGACUUUACACUGUGGUUUAUAAUAUAAGCAUAUUUAUAAUACAUUAAUGUUUUUAUUAAA